UAAAAAUAGUUUUGAUUAUUUUCCUGUUUACAUUUAGAAAAAGUGCAAAGGGCACUGUAUGGCUUUUUGUAUGAGACAUUUUGGCCUGUGACCAUGAUAAAGGGUUCUGGUACAUAGCACUGGGUGAUCUGGGCAUAUUCUAAGAUAUGUGCUACAUAUGAGAGAGUCAGGUCCUCUGUUUUCUGGUACAUCCUUCAGCCACUGUUACAGGGUCCUUUACAGCAGUCCUUCAGCCUUGUUCUCAUAUAUUGCUGCUUCUCAGAGCAUGAGCCUUCCAAAACAUAAAAUCCAAUAGUCUGAGUCAUACACCACUUUUGGUACCCGAAGCCUUAACCACCUUCUCUGGCUAUUUUGUUUAGACACGCGAAAAAAGAGCUAUUUGCAUCCUUCAUCCUGGACAAUAAAGCUGUUAAUCUGCUCUCCAACAGGAGGCUGCCUUUUGAUUGUCUCCACAGAGCCUUAACAUUGCUUCCCUGUGUUGGAUGGGAGGGUAGUGGCACCUUCUGUCCUCCUCACUCAGUUACUCUUAGGAGUUAUCCAUCUCAGGCCAUUCAAAGAGCAGAAUCAAAACACAGCAAUGCAAUUUUAAUCUUAGGCAGGAUAUCUCAUUCCAUAACUCACAUUCCUUUCAAAGUCAAAGUUUUUCAAAACUAAAUUUACUAUUUUACUUCCUCCAACUUGACCCUCUUCUUAUAUUCUAUAUCUUAUGUAAUCACCAAGUUCAAACCAGAAAACAGGGAGUCAGUUGAUUCUACCUCCAUAAUACCUCUGGAGUCCUCCCCCAUCUCUCAGUUCCCACUGCUGCUGACUUAGACUGAGCCCAUUUUACCUCUCAGCUGGUUACGUUCUUCUUUACUGCCUCCCUUUCUGAUCAUUCACAAAAGCUACUGAGAUUUUCUUAAAAUGCAAGUCAGAACAUGUAGCUCUUCUUUUAAAGCUCUUUCUUGGCUCUUUGUUACUAUCAUGGUACAGUUGUUUAACAUGGCCUAAGAAUUUCACCUGUUUGCCUCUCUAGCCUUAGCUCUCCCACAAAACUUCUUUUGGUAUCUAGAAUUCAUAAUUCUUUUCUUAUUUGUUGGUUUUUAUGCCUCUUAACCUGCAGUUCUUGAAAGAACUACUCAUCCCUUCUUUGCUGAGGCAGUUCCUGCUAUCUUUCUUAACCAGCUCCAAUAGGCUUUUCUUAUUUUCCUCAAAGCUAGGUUUGGUGUUUUUCCAGUAGUCUCACAGCAUCUUGUAACCACUCUCCCCUUCUACCAAACCAUAUUUUAAUUAUUUUCACUUUUGUUUCUCCUACUAGACUUGAGAUAGUUAUUAUAAAAACCAGAGUGGAACACAGUGACUGCGGUCACUAGAUAAAUACCUUCAUGUUUAGUUGGUUUAUUAGAAUUGAAACUAACUUUAUGAUGAUAAAAAACAAGUACAUAUCCAACAUGGUUAAAAUAAGCUAUUCUGUUAUCUUCUGUGGGGAGAGUGUGGAGAAGUGCAUUGAUGAAUACUUCUGAAAUCAGAAUAAUGAACCAUGAUUAGACAUUUUAAUAAAUAAUACUAAUAAUUUGUUGCUUCUCCAAAAUGUCAAAGGUCCAAAUUUUAUAAUUUCUAUUUCUGCAUGUGCAGUUUGCCCUCAAGGAGACUAAAAGCAAACAUGCCUUAAAAAUUAGCCUCUCGGGAUUGUAAGAAGCUCAUUUUACAAUAGAAGGUACACAUAAUAUUUGAUCUGACUUGAAGUUUUUAUUCUGGAUAUCAAAAGAGUUACAACUAAGAAAUUCAAAGAUAAUAAAAAUAAUGUUAAAUCAUUAAAGUAAGGGAAGUUAUGUAAAACUUUUGGCUUUUCAUAAAAGAAAAGAAACUAUAAUUCAACCAUAUUCUUUUUAAAGGCCCAUUGGUAUAUCUACCUCAUAACGCAGUGUAAUCUAAUCUGAAACUCAGCCAACUUAAGUGGCCAUCAUAGAAAGCUCUGUGGUUUUUUUAAUCACACAUUUCUUGACUUUAUAGAAAAGGUUCCUGAAGACUCAUAUUAAGAAAGCUAAAGAAGUAAUUUAUUUGUCGUCUUCAAAUGCUGAGAACACUAAAUAGAUGAAUUCACACACCUUUGAACACUGCAAAUAUAGGGAACCUUCACUUUGCAUGGCCCCAAUAUGCUCAAAUAUCAGUUACUGUGUUUAGCUAAAUAACACCAGUCCCACAGUACAAUUCACAUUUUAGUUACCACAAUAUAUUCACUGCAAGUAAUUGCCUAAAGUAGUAAGCAUCUUUGCUGGCACUUUAGUCCACAAGUCCCUAUGUAAAUAACAGAUGUGCAUCAUGACCAGUGACUAAUAAAUGUUACUUCUUUCAAAAUAUGUCAGUGAUAGGUAACUGUGAGCCUCUUAUUCAGUUCACACACAGCAAAGCAUGUGAUUGUAUUGUCUCCUUGUCUCUCAAUGGUAAACCCCUAUGACCUUUUACCAAAAUGUAUAAUCAAGAGAGAGAUUUGGCUGAGAGAGAUGAAACUGCAAUAAAGGGAUAAAAAGUGAUAAUGUUGGAAAUGAAAUUUGAAUGGAGUUAUAGAAGAACUAGCUGACCAGGGACAUGCUGACACUGCUACUGCUCAAAAGACCCUAGAGCUGCAGCCUAAGGCACCUGUGGAAGGGGAACUUACCGACAUGAAUGACCAAAGUGCUUGUGAGGAAAAGGAUAAAGGCAACCUAGGGGAAGCAAUGAUGGUAGAAAACUUGACAUUAAAGAAACUUUGGAGCUAUUUCACAGCAAUAUAAGUGCCAAGGAUAAAAGGUGGAAACUGAUCCAGACUUGGAAGUUAGCCUAGACAUAGAAAAAAUGCUCACUCUGUAUUGUAAGUUAUACAACAAAAAGAAGAGGCAAACACUGUUCAAACUACUCUGGAUGAUUCAACACGCGUUCCUCUUGGAAAAAGCAAGGACUACAUCAAUGCUAGUUAUAUUAGAAUAGUCAAUUGUGGAGAAGAGUAUUUUUAUAUCGCUACUCAAGGACCACUGCUGAGCACCAUAGAUGACUUUUGGCAAAUGGUGUUGGAAAAUAAUUCAAAUGUUAUUGCCAUGAUAACCAGAGAGAUAGAAGGUGGAAUUAUCAAAUGCUACCAUUACUGGCCCAUUUCUCUGAAGAAGCCAUUGGAAUUGAAACACUUCCGUGUAUUCCUGGAGAACUACCAGAUACUUCAAUAUUUCAUCAUUCGAAUGUUUCAAGUUGUGGAGAAGUCCACGGGAACUAGUCACUCUGUAAAACAGUUGCAGUUCACCAAGUGGCCAGACCAUGGCACUCCUGCCUCAGCAGAUAGCUUCAUAAAAUAUAUUCGUUAUGCAAGGAAGAGCCACCUUACAGGACCCAUGGUUGUUCACUGCAGUGCCGGCAUAGGCCGGACAGGGGUGUUCCUAUGUGUGGAUGUCGUGUUCUGUGCCAUCGUAAAGAACUGUUCAUUCAACAUCAUGGAUAUAGUGGCCCAAAUGAGAGAACAACGUUCUGGCAUGGUUCAAACGAAGGAGCAGUAUCACUUUUGUUACGAUAUUGUGCUUGAAGUUCUUCGGAAACUUCUGACUUUGGAUUAAGAAAGACUUCUGUUGCCUCUCACUUGAAAUUACCAAGUGGGUUUGCACCUCCUCAUAAAGAACAUGUUUGCACUGUGCUGAAGGGCUUUGCUAUGCAUACAAUCUGCUUUCUUGGUUUAUCAGUUUAUUUUCUUUCUAAAAGCUCCCUGAAGGGCAAUAUCAUUUGGCUUGGGGUGAUCAGUGUUUACUUAUUGAUCUUGCUAGACAAUAUCAAAAUAACUUCCCACAUUUUCCAGUGAAACAGAUGUUACAUAAAACGAUUGCAGCUUGGCUAUUUGGUUGAAGGGAUUACAGAGCCCAAUAAAGGAUUUAAAAUAUAUUCAUUAAGAUUUUAUUUGGAAAGGUGGCUGGAGAGAGCUGAGGAUUUCCAGGACUUUGUAAGUUCUUAUUCUGGGAGAACAUAAGGCCAAUAAUCAUGACCUCUUCCAGGCAUUUUUAAGACAGAUGUCUAUUCAUGUUCUUUAGCUAGAGCCUGUACUUUUUGCUGGCAUUUGAAUAACCCAGUUUAAAAAGAGUCCAGUUAGGGUGGACUAACUUUGGACACAAAUUGGCUUCCAUUUCCUACAUUUUCAUACUGCUGCCUUCCUACAGCUGCUAGACCAAGACCUGUUGGUCUGGGAAGCAUUUCAUGGAUAGGGAGAGCUCCUCUCGGUGAACAGUCCAAAACUAAAAUAGAUGUUUAUAUAGAAAGCCCAAGAGGAGACUUUUGCCAUGCCUGAGUUCUUUCCUAUCCCACCCUAACACUUAACAUAUUACUUAGUCUGCUUUGUUAAAAGCAAGUAUUACCUUUAACUUGCCUCUUACUCUUUGCCCUUUAGCUAACUAAUAAAGUUUGAUAUAGGCAUUAUUAUAUAAUUCUGAGUCAUUCAUGGUAUCUCUCAUGUUUGAUGUAUUUUUCAAACUAAGAUCUAUGAUAGUUUUUUUUCCAGAGUUCCAUUAAAUCAUUUAUUUCCUUUACUUUCUCACCUCUGUUGAAACAUUUAGAAACUGGAUUUGGGAACCCAAUUUUGGAAAACCAGAUUCAUAGUCAUGAAAAUGGAAACUUCCAUAUUCUGUUUUUGAAAAGAUGUGGCCAUUAUUACAGUAAUUUUAUUAUAGGACUUUGCCUCGUACAAUUAAUAGUGAUAUUUUGGACAAGGAGUUCUGGUGACAAGCUAUACCUAAUUAUAAGCUAUAAAACAAUAGAUAUGAGUGUUUGUACAGUUUAACUCAAUGGAGAUCAGAAUAUUCUAUGUAUUGAGAAAAUGUUUAAUAUCAAUCUAUAAAUCUUGAAUUUCUAAGAGGCUUAUUUUGUUCUUUUGGCUGAAUGAGUAUAUUUGAAUUGGUUGAAUAAUUAAUAAUUCUCAUUGUAAAAAUAAUUAUAUGCCAAAAAUAUAUUUGAUGUUAAAUCAAAUAGAUGAUUCUGUUUACAUUGUUCAUAUGAAUAAUAAUCUGUGUUAAUUUCAUUUUGAUAAUUGGCCUUUAAUAUUUGUAUCUCUAAUUUUAUUUUCUCUCUGUUACUGUAAAAUAAUAGCUAUAAUGUAUAACAAUUUUCUUCAGAAGAAUUCUAUGCUAUUAUUAAAAUAAAAUAUUUACUGUGUA